ACUCAACCUCUGAAUGUUAGUGACACUAUUGGGACGAAAAAGGACUGUGCUGGCCCAAAUGGCAGGCAUCUCAUAUGUGGCAUCUUUCUUUCUCCUUCUGACUAAGCUCAGCAUUGGCCAGAGAGAAGUAACAGUUCAGAAAGGACCACUGUUUAGAGCUGAAGGUUACCCAGUCAGCAUUGGCUGCAAUGUAACUGGCCACCAGGGACCUUCUGAGCAGCAUUUCCAGUGGUCUGUUUACCUGCCGACAAACCCGACCCAGGAAGUCCAGAUCAUUAGCACCAAGGAUGCUGCCUUCUCUUACGCAGUAUAUACGCAGCGGGUGCGAAGCGGAGACGUCUACGUGGAGAGGGUCCAGGGCAACUCAGUCUUGUUGCACAUCUCAAAACUCCAGAUGAAGGAUGCUGGCGAGUAUGAGUGUCACACACCAAACACUGAUGAGAAAUACUAUGGAAGUUACAGUGCAAAGACUAAUCUAAUUGUUAUUCCAGAUACCCUCUCUGCCACCAUGAGUUCUCAGACUCUCGGUAAGGAGGAAGGUGAGCCAUUAGCCCUCACCUGUGAGGCAUCCAAAGCCACAGCCCAACAUACUCACCUCUCUGUCACCUGGUACCUAACACAGGAUGGAGGAGGAAGCCAAGCCACUGAGAUUAUUUCUCUCUCCAAAGAUUUUAUAUUGGUCCCUGGGCCCUUGUAUACAGAGCGGUUUGCAGCCAGUGACGUACAGCUCAACAAACUGGGACCCACUACAUUCAGGCUGUCCAUAGAGAGGCUCCAGUCCUCAGAUCAGGGUCAGCUGUUCUGUGAGGCAACGGAAUGGAUUCAGGAUCCAGAUGAAACUUGGAUGUUCAUCACCAAAAAGCAGACCGAUCAAACCACUCUGAGGAUCCAGCCAGCAGUGAAAGAUUUUCAAGUCAACAUUACAGCUGACAGCUUGUUUGCUGAAGGGAAACCCUUAGAACUGGUUUGCCUGGUUGUAAGCAGUGGCCGUGACCCACAGCUUCAAGGCAUUUGGUUCUUCAAUGGGACUGAAAUUGCUCACAUUGAUGCUGGUGGAGUCCUGGGCCUGAAGAAUGACUACAAAGAGAGAGCAAGUCAAGGAGAGCUCCAGGUUUCAAAGUUAGGCCCCAAGGCUUUCUCUCUCAAGAUCUUCUCUCUGGGCCCAGAGGAUGAAGGCGCCUACAGAUGUGUGGUAGCAGAGGUCAUGAAAACACGCACAGGUUCCUGGCAGGUGCUUCAGAGAAAGCAGUCACCAGACAGCCACGUGCACCUGAGGAAGCCAGCAGCAAGAAGUGUGGUCAUGUCUACCAAGAACAAGCAGCAAGUUGUGUGGGAAGGAGAGACACUCGCCUUUCUCUGUAAGGCUGGUGGAGCUGAAAGUCCCCUGUCUGUGAGCUGGUGGCACAUCCCACGGGACCAGACACAGCCCGAGUUUGUGGCUGGCAUGGGGCAGGAUGGCAUUGUGCAGCUGGGUGCCUCCUAUGGGGUACCCAGUUACCAUGGCAACACAAGGCUGGAGAAAAUGGACUGGGCCACCUUCCAGCUGGAGAUCACCUUCACUGCCAUCACAGACAGUGGCACAUAUGAGUGCAGAGUAUCUGAGAAGUCUCGGAACCAGGCCAGAGAUCUGAGCUGGACUCAGAAGAUUUCAGUUACUGUAAAGUCUCUGGAGUCAAGUUUACAAGUUAGUCUGAUGAGCCGUCAGCCGCAAGUGAUGUUAACCAACACCUUUGACCUGUCCUGUGUCGUGAGGGCCGGUUACUCUGACCUCAAGGUGCCACUCACUGUGACGUGGCAGUUCCAGCCAGCUAGCUCUCACAUCUUCCACCAGCUUAUUCGAAUCACCCACAAUGGCACUAUUGAAUGGGGGAAUUUCCUAUCCCGGUUCCAAAAGAAGACGAAAGUGUCGCAGUCUUUAUUUCGUUCACAACUCCUAGUCCAUGAUGCCACUGAGGAAGAGACAGGAGUGUAUCAGUGUGAAGUAGAAGUUUAUGACAGAAAUUCCCUAUACAACAACCGCCCCCCGAGGGCUUCUGCCAUCUCUCACCCACUGAGGAUAGCCGUCACUUUACCAGAGAGCAAGCUAAAAGUGAAUUCAAGGAGUCAAGUCCAAGAGCUCUCCAUCAACUCCAACACUGAUAUAGAAUGUAGCAUCUUGUCCCGGUCCAAUGGAAACCUUCAGUUAGCCAUUAUUUGGUAUUUUUCUCCUGUUUCCACUAAUGCCUCUUGGCUAAAGAUCCUGGAGAUGGACCAAACCAAUGUUAUAAAAACUGGGGAUGAGUUUCACACCCCACAGAGAAAACAAAAAUUUCAUACUGAGAAGGUUUCCCAAGACUUAUUUCAGCUGCACAUUCUGAAUGUGGAAGACAGCGAUCGGGGCAAAUAUCACUGUGCUGUGGAGGAAUGGCUCCUGUCUACAAAUGGCACUUGGCACAAGCUUGGAGAAAAGAAGUCAGGACUAACAGAAUUGAAACUCAAGCCCACAGGAAGUAAGGUACGUGUCUCCAAAGUGUACUGGACCGAAAAUGUGACUGAGCACAGAGAAGUGGCCAUCCGCUGCAGCCUGGAGAGUGUAGGCAGCUCAGCCACUCUGUACUCUGUGAUGUGGUACUGGAACAGAGAAAACUCUGGAAGUAAAUUGCUGGUGCACUUGCAACAUGAUGGCUUGCUGGAGUAUGGGGAAGAGGGGCUCAGGAGGCACCUGCACUGUUACCGUUCAUCCUCUACAGACUUUGUCCUGAAGCUUCAUCAGGUGGAGAUGGAGGAUGCAGGAAUGUACUGGUGUAGGGUGGCAGAGUGGCAGCUCCAUGGACACCCAAGCAAGUGGAUUAAUCAAGCAUCCGAUGAGUCACAGCGGAUGGUGCUCACGGUGCUGCCUUCAGAGCCCACGCUUCCUUCCAGGAUCUGCUCCUCGGCCCCUUUACUCUAUUUCCUGUUCAUCUGUCCCUUCGUCCUGCUCCUCCUUCUGCUCAUCUCCCUCCUCUGCUUAUACUGGAAGGCCAGGAAGUUGUCAACACUGCGUUCCAACACACGGAAAGAAAAAGCUCUCUGGGUGGACUUGAAAGAGGCUGGAGGUGUGACCACAAAUAGGAGGGAAGACGAGGAGGAAGAUGAAGGCAACUGAAUCCCAAGAGGCACCUGCAGCCAGGAAGGAAAGGUGGGGGCUUUUUAAUUGGGCUAACCAGGGUGUGAAUGAAUCCUGGUUCUGUCCUCAACUAUGUCUGCGGCCUUGGGCAAGUUACCUAGGAAUCAGAGGGAGCAUUCACUGAGUGCUUAUUGGUUCUACGCACUGUUAGGUGUUCCUUUGUGUCUUACCUCAUCCACCUCUCGCAUCCCCCCUUGGAACAAGAUAGCAUCAUUACCCUACAUCUCUUGAAGGUUCAGGUCCCUGGGCUGCAAGGAGAUAAGAGGCUCCCUCACACAGCCUCUGGAGGGCUAAAUGAGAUCCUACAGCAAUGCCCUGGUGGGGCUUCUCUCUCCCUCUUAUGUCACUUGUCACACCUGCUCUAGGUAAUCAUUUUCCUCCAGAUGAGAGGUGUAGGAAAGGACCUGAUGCCAGCAAGGAAAAAGGAAUUGGUAACAUGCUCUUUGUUUACCUAAAAUCUGUCCCCACAACAAGAAUGUAACUUCCUUCGAGGCAGAAAUUCAAUUUUCUUCUCCCAGCCCACCUACAAAGGCCCACUCAAGAGCAAGUUCUGUGUAAAGGUGCUUAACUAAUACAGGUUCUUUGACAAAAUGAUAAAACAUUUGUAACCUGAGUUUGGGGCUUUUUGUUUAUUGUUUGAUAAGACUUUUUAUUAAGUAAUUGCUGAGCAAAAACUUUGUAAAAACUCAUGUAACAGUACUCCAGUCAGCCCCCCAAGGCCUCGUACCCCUGCUUCCCCCUACACCUCCAUAUCCCCACCAAAAGGUCCAUCUGGCUCCUGGUGCUCAGCCAGUGCCUUAUUUUCUUUGACCUGACAGCACUGGGUGGUAGGGAAGGUAUUGUCUGGAGGAGCAGGGUUGACAGUGCCACCGUUCCCUCAUACGCCUGCAGGGCUGGGGUUUGGGGCAGCAGUAGGUCAAGUCUGGUUCCUCAAGGUCUCCUAUUCUCAGUAGCAAAAAGCAGCCGGUGGGGGUGGGGUGUAAUGGCUUAAAGCUUUCAACAGCUGUCCCCACUGGGCCUACAGUCCCCUCAUCUUUGUUUCAAAAGCCGCUCAGGCCCUGUUGUAGCCAGAAUUGGAAAUCAAUCAGUGCCACCUAAAGACUUGAGAAAACACAUCUAUUUAUUAUCUAUGUGACCAACCGAGUUGCUUUAACACUCGUUAAUUUGCAUUUCCAAGGAGAGCAAUUUAGUUUUAAUUAUUUGAUCAGGCACACACGUCCUCUCCAAACAUAAUUAGUUCCUUCCUAAGGGGAUUAUUGGUGGCUAUGAGCACUCCUACUAUGGACCUACCAGUUCCUUAAACUCAUGUCCCUUCAUAGCCUGAUUUAAAAUACUCCAAAUCUUUCCUUAAACAUGUCAGCACAUUUGUUUCUUGUCAUCCAGGUAAGGGAGCAUAUUUUUACAAACAACAAAGCUGAAAUGAAGACUUUUUUUUUUUUUUUUUUGAGAUGAAGUCUCGCUCUGUCGCCCGGGCUGGAGUGCAGUGGUGUGACCUGGGCUCACUGCAAGCUCCGCCUCCCGGGUUCACGCCAUCCUCCUGCCUCAGCCUCCCAAGUAGCUGGGACUACAGGCACCCGCCACCAUGCCUGGCUAAUUUUUUUUUGUAUUUUUAGUAGAGACGGGGUUUCACCGUGUUAGCCAGGAUGGUCUCGAUCUCCUGACUUCAUGAUCCACCCGCCUCGGCCUCCCAAAGUGCUGGGAUUACAGGCGUGAGCCACCACGCCCGGCAGAAGACUCUUAGAAAGUGUGAUGACCCCCUGCCCCUAUUUUUUAGAAACCUGUAUUUUAAUUCAAAGGGAAAGAGAGCAGAAGUGAGCCUGGGCAGAGAAUCUUGGAUGGACUCUGCUGCAGCCCUCUGUGGGAGCACUCUUCACCCCAUCCCUCCUCUCUGCUCACAUGGACACCUCCUUCAAGCUUCUAGCUCAAACACCUCUUCCCCUUUUGAAUCCAGCACAGAGAUAGCACAGAGGAGAUGUAAGCAGACAGGGAGGGUCUCCUGGGAAAGCAGACAUUUAACCAACUUGAGCAAUCAGCUUGUUUUACAGCUUCCUGCCUUGCUGCCUGUUUCUUCCCAAGCCCCGUGUGGAAUGUGGUGACCUAGUCACCUGGAACCAGCUCCUGACAGACCCCGGCAACUUCUAGAUGAACCCAAGUGAACUUUCCUCAUUACCAUCCUGAAGUCACUACCCCAGGGGGAGCUAUAGCUUCAUGACCGUAACAUGUGACCUGUGUGCUGGCAGGACGACUCACUGCGGCUGCGCCACUGGGACCCCUCCCCUACAUGCACCAAUGCACUCUCUCCCCUCUCCAUCACCCCAUAAAACCCUCCUGUCACUUUCCUUCAGAGACACCGCUUUGGAGAGUAUUCCCAGCGCUCUCCUUGCUUGUGACAAGUAAAAAAAAAAAAAAACUCCUUUUCAUCAAAACUCA